AUUGAUGAAAAUUGGGUUACCCUGAGGACUCUUGCUUAACUGAAAUCACAAAUGGAGCAGACAGAAAAAUCAAAAGUAUAUGCUGAGAACGGACUCUUAGAAAAGAUAAAGCUUUGCCUUUCAAAGAAACCACUGCCAUCUCCCACUGAGCGAAAGAAGUUUGACCAUGACUUUGCCAUCUCCACUUCCUUUCAUGGGAUACACAAUAUUGUUCAGAACCGGAGCAAAAUUCGCAGGGUGCUCUGGUUGGUGGUGGUUCUGGGCUCAGUCUCACUUGUGACAUGGCAGAUCUACAUUCGCUUGCUCAACUACUUCACAUGGCCAACCACAACGUCCAUUGAGGUUCAAUAUGUGGAAAAGAUGGAGUUCCCAGCUGUGACAUUUUGUAAUUUGAACAGGUUCCAAACAGAUGCUGUAGCCAAAUUUGGUGUUAUUUUUUUCUUAUGGCACAUUGUAUCCAAAGUCCUCCAUCUUCAAGAAAUUACUGCCAAUUCCACUGGCUCUAGAGAGGCUACUGAUUUUGCUGCAAGUCACCAAAACUUCAGCAUUGUGGAAUUUAUCAGGAACAAAGGUUUUUAUCUCAACAAUAGCACUUUGUUGGACUGUGAGUUUUUUGGAAAGCCAUGUAGCCCAAAGGAUUUUGCACAUGUCUUCACUGAAUAUGGAAAUUGUUUUACUUUUAAUCAUGGUGAAACUCUCCAAGCAAAGAGAAAAGUGAGUGUCUCUGGAAGAGGUUUGAGCUUACUCUUCAAUGUGAAUCAGGAGGCAUUCACUGAUAACCCAGCCCUUGGUUUCGUUGAUGCUGGGAUCAUCUUUGUUAUCCAUUCACCAAAGAAGGUGCCACAGUUUGAUGGGUUAGGCUUGUUGUCACCUGUGGGAAUGCACGCAAGGGUAACCAUCCGCCAAGUGAAGACAGUUCAUCAAGAAUACCCUUGGGGAGAAUGCAAUCCUAACAUCAAGCUGCAGAAUUUUAGCAGCUACAGCACUUCUGGUUGCUUGAAGGAAUGCAAAGCCCAGCACAUAAAAAAGCAAUGUGGAUGUGUGCCUUUUCUUCUUCCUGGAUAUGGGAUAGAAUGUGACCUACAAAAGUACUUCAGCUGUGUUUCUCCUGUACUUGACCACAUUGAAUUUAAGGAUUUAUGUACAGUAGGAACACAUAACUCUAGCUGCCCCGUUUCUUGUGAAGAAAUAGAAUACCCGGCCACUAUUUCUUAUUCCUCUUUUCCAAGUCAAAAAGCUUUGAAAUAUCUUUCCAAGAAGUUGAAUCAAAGCCGGAAAUACAUCAGGUAACCUUACUAGCUUUUAAAUAUUGAAAUUAAUAG